GAGCCCUGCCUGCGCCCGCCCCCGAAGCGGCGCGGGACGCCUGGCGCCGUCCGCGAUCCGCAGGGCUGCCCGCUUAGGCUUAGGCCCGGCCCGCUGGCAAAGCCGAGCCGCAGCAUUUUAUUUCGUUCGUGGUUUCCGCACAGGCUGGAGUUUCGUGGGUUGGGUCGUACUUGGGACCUCGGCGAAGAGGACCCGUUUAUUUUUUUUUCUUUCCAAAAUGGCAGCCUCCAGUCGCGCACAAGUGUUAUCUCUGUACCGGGCGAUGCUGAGAGAGAGCAAGCGUUUCAGCGCCUACAAUUACAGAACAUAUGCUGUCAGGAGGAUAAGAGAUGCCUUCAGAGAAAAUAAAAAUGUAAAGGAUCCUGUAGAAAUUCAAACCCUAGUGAAUAAAGCCAAGAGAGACCUUGGAGUAAUUCGUCGACAGAGACACUCAAACUGGGAUUCUGGUCAUGGCCAGGUGACUGCCAUGAGGACAGAGGCAUCUGGCGUUAGUUCCUGGAUGAAGGCUGUACAGGAAGCAUGGUGCCAGCAUCUGCUUCUGCUAAGGGGUUCAGGCUGCUUCCGCUCAUGGCAGAAGGCGCAGGGGAGCCGGCGAGUCACAUGGUGAGAGAGGAAGCAAGAGAGAGAGGAGGAGAUGCCAGGCUCUUUUUAACAAUCAGUUCUCAUGGGAACUCAGAAGAGCAAGAACUCAUUCAUUACUGCAAGGAUGACUCCAAGCCAUUCAUGAGGGACCAGAUUCCAUAACCCAAACACCGCCCACCAGGCCCCAUCUCCCACACUGGGGAUCACAUUUCAACAUGAGACUUGGAUGGGACAAACAUCCAAACUGUAUCAGACAUCAUCUCACGAAUCCACAAAUUUAGCUGCUUUCCCUUCUUUUCUGUAGUUUCACAACCUACUAUAGAAGCACUUUCUAGAGGGGCCUGCAGAAGUGAAUUUCCUCUUCCAUGGCCUCGAUGUAUUUGGCUGUUGAUUCAGUAUCACUGAACUUACUGCCAACAGCACUACAACUCACGCUGAAGGCACCUCAUCCAGCACAGGUAUUGUCUCCACAGGCACAUCGCAGCCUCCUGCACUCAGAGACAGUAGACAGCACUUCAGCACCGUGCCUGGGGACAUUUUAAACAGCAAAAUCACCAACAAAAGUACAAAAAUGCAAAAGCAUGGCUCUGGAUAGACAGCAGGAAGGACCACUUGUUUCUAGUGUGAGAGCUGGGACAAGAAAGCAGAGGGGUCACCUUGCUUCACCUCAGCCGGGAACAGAUGCCUUGGACUACUCAGAUUUUUUCCCUGCUCUGUACAAGUCUGUGAAUCACUGUGAAGCCACAAGUAUUGAUUUGGUUUACAAACACAUUUUAGUGAAGAGGUGAAUUUGCAGGUAUGGAAUCUAGAAAUAAUGAGAUCGGACUGUAAGGCUGGAGACGAAGAUGGAGAGGCUGCUGCCAAGUGACAGGCUGGCUCUUGUCCCAGAAGCUGUGGACUGCCACUGGAGUGUUUCAAGCAAGGGAGUGGCUUGAUCUGUGUUGUAGGAACAGCACCUUUUCUCAACUUAAAAGUGUGGCUUGAAGAGAGGAAGACGGGAGACUGGUUAGGAGAUGGAUGUAUCCAGGUGAGGAUGAGGGUGGGUGAACGGAGCCAGGGAUAGAGGUCCUCAGGGGAGCUGACCUGAGACCCCUGUGAGUCUCGGGUCCUGGCAAUGGGGCGGCGGUGAGUGGUGAGGGGGAGGCAUUGAGGACAGCGCCCGGGGUCCCCGGCUGGGGCACAUGCUGGGGUGUAGGGCAGUGGUCAAGGGCCCUAGCCUUGCAGUCAGACACCCCUGGCGGGCUGUGUGGCUUAGACAUGCUCCUCCACUUCCCUAAGCCUAGUUGUUUCAUGUCUAGCAUAAAGAUUCCGUGUGGCAGGAAGAACACACCCCCGGGAGUGAUUCUGAGAUUGAAAUGAGUGCUGGUGCUUUUCACCUAAACAAGGAAAACGGGGAGAGAAGCAGUAUGUGGGGUGGGAGGGAGAAGAGUCUGUCUGGGCGUGGGGAUUUGGACGUGCCUCUGGACACCCAUGGACAAAUAUCCUGAGGCCAUCUGAUGUUUUCCGGGGGCCACGGGAGUGGGGGAGGGGAAGGUGGGGCGGAGACACAGACUUGGGCAUUACCAGCAGGCAGGGGGCUGCUACCGCCAUGAAGAGUGGGCAGUGCCAGGAUCAGAGGGCCGGGGUAAAGCCUGCGGAAUUCCCACAUUUCAGAAGAGGCUGGGAAGGAGGUCAAGGAAGAGCAGCAGGAGGAGGAGAAAGCAGGAGGGUGUGGAGGGACGGGAGGCGGGGAGGAGGAAUUCCAGGAGGGAGUGGCCGGGGUGACUGUUCUGAAAGCAUGGACUGGAAGCCACAGCACAUUUGGGCUGCAAGGAACCCGAGAGAUCUUCUAGUCUAAUCCUCUUUCAGUCUCCAUCCCCGUCCGGAUGAAGACAGCGAGAUCCAAAAGUAAAGUCAGUUGUACUGUGACUUCCUAGCAGGAUACCCUAACUCCUAAUUCAUAAUAAAACUACAGACAUUCUCAAUUCAAAAUUCUUCCUAUUCAGUCACACUGGACUUUCUCCCAAUGUGACAAAAUUAUUGAGAUUUUAUUGACUUACUGAACAACUGUGGUCUUUGCCAUGUACUAAGAUACUGUGUAGUCAAACUGCGCCUCUGAAAUCUAUUUUUAUUGUACAUUUAACAAAUUUUGCUGUAAACAAUAAGUUUAAAAACAAUAGUCAUAACUCAUUAAACUGUAUCUUUUAAUUUUAAUAUGUUAUUAUACCUCAAUGAAACUCAGUUUUAAAAAACAGUGAAUAAAAAGUUGAGCUAUUAAAACUAAAAAGUAAUUAUUUGCUAGUUUGUAUACACAGACCCAAGAAAUAGAAAUAUAGGAAUAUUUGGAACUUGCUCCUUCUUACAGCCUUGAGGGAACCGCUUAUCCCUUAUUACGCCUUGGUUUCCCUCAAUGAAACUAGAAAAUAUUACCUUGCAAGACGCUCAUAGUUAAUUAAUACGUAUGAAGCUCUUGAAUCUAAAUAUUAAAUACUUGAUGAUAUUGUCUGGUAAAUAUUAUCUAACUGCAUUUAUAAAUACUAGCAUUUUUACAGCCUAGUGGUAAUUACAAAGUAUAGCCCAUUUAAAAUGAAUACAAAUAUGUGCAUAUAUAUUUUUCCUGUGAAAGUAGGAAAAGAAAGUUGAAAUUAUGCAAGAACAAAGUAGAAAAAUAUGCCUCUCAUAUAAGAUUGAGUGUUUCCAUUGAUCAAUAUAAUUUUUAAAAUGUUGUGAUGAUUCUUUUUUUCACUUAAUUGGCUAUGUCAUUUGCACUCUACCUAAGUGAGAUAUUAAUAAAUUGUAUAUGAUGUAAAUAACAGGAAACAAGAAGAACUGCUGGCCUUAUUCAUAGUUAAUAAAGAGAACCAGAUGAUGAAA